AGAGGCCGGCGCCUUUAAGAAGGGGCGGGUUCGUGCCCUCCAUUCAGGCCCUUGGGCCUCGGCCAUUGAUGAACCUGCGGGCUGCGCGGGCCGGAACCGCGCCAGCCCAGCGGGCUGAAGCCGGGCAGAGGCAGGGACGCAUCCUGGCCCCCUGCAGCCCCGAAGUGGGGGCCUUCAGGGAGGGAAGUCUGCAGUGACUGGAGCCUCUCAGGAGCCACGCAAGGCAGACCGGGCAGCCCCAGGCGAGACUCUGAACACGAAUAAGCCAGGAUCUACGUGCACUUCGAGCUAGUGCAAGGGAGAGCCUCAGGCUAGGCUGUCAGACCUGGGUGGAGCCCUACCAAUGCCCCCGAGCCAACAUCACCUACCCUGUAAAAUGGGAUGGUGCUGCCUGCCUCCUGGCUAAGGGACCGGCAACUCCCGGCAGGAAUUGCGUCCCAGAGUCAGGUCCCUGGAGCUCCUCUGGGAGGACUGGGGGCAGGGGGUGUGGUUUCCCCAAGAGGUUUUGACUGCCUCUUGAGCUGAAGCCCCCACUACUGUGUCCCACCUUGAACUCUCCCAACCUCUUCCCUCCUGGCCUCCCCACUCCACGCAGGAAGAGGUUGGGAGAGUGACCUAGAACUUUUCAGCUCCAGGAGCUUUGGGAGAGGUCUGGUGGUGGCGGUGGUGGCACUUCUUUUAGGCUAGUGUGGAUCAGGGCAUUUUUGGGGGUCUCAGAGACAGUUUCCCACCAGCUACUUCCUUAGAGGUCUGUCCUACCAACAUACAAGAACAGCCCCACCCCGUGGCAGGCCGGCUUCUGAUGCUGCUUGGUUGAAUGCUUCUAGCCGCAGGUGGCUGCGAUGGGACGGAAGCCAUGAAUGGUGCCGGCCCUGGCCCCGCCGCAGCCGCCCCGGUCCCAGUCCCGGUCCCGGUCCCGGACUGGCGGCAGUUCUGCGAGCUGCAUGCGCAGGCGGCCGCCGUGGACUUUGCGCACAAGUUCUGCCGUUUCCUGCGGGACAACCCAGCUUACGACACGCCCGACGCCGGCGCCUCCUUCUCCCGCCACUUCGCCGCCAACUUCCUGGACGUCUUCGGCGAGGAGGUGCGCCGCGUGCUGGUGGCUGGGCCGACGACUCGGGGCGCGGCCGUGAGCGCAGAGGCCAUGGAGCCGGAGCUCGCGGACACCUCUGCACUCAAGGCGGCGCCCUACGGCCACUCGCGGAGCUCGGAGGACGUGUCCACGCACGCGGCCACCAAGGCCCGCGUUCGCAAGGGCUUCUCGCUGCGCAACAUGAGCCUGUGCGUGGUGGACGGCGUGCGCGACAUGUGGCACCGGCGCGCCUCGCCCGAGCCCGACGCGGCAGCUGCCCCGCGCACCGCCGAGCCCCGCGACAAGUGGACGCGGCGCCUGAGGCUGUCGCGGACGCUGGCUGCCAAGGUGGAGCUGGUGGACAUUCAACGCGAGGGGGCGCUGCGCUUCAUGGUGGCCGACGACGCGGCCGCGGGCUCCGGGGGCUCGGCUCAGUGGCAGAAGUGCCGCCUGCUCCUGCGCAGGGCUGUGGCCGAGGAACGCUUCCGCCUGGAGUUCUUCGUGCCGCCCAAAGCCUCCAGGCCCAAGGUCAGCAUCCCACUGUCAGCCAUCAUUGAGGUCCGCACCACCAUGCCCCUGGAAAUGCCAGAGAAGGAUAACACAUUCGUCCUCAAGGUAGAGAAUGGAGCCGAAUACAUCUUGGAGACCAUCGACUCUCUGCAGAAGCACUCGUGGGUAGCUGACAUCCAGGGCUGCGUGGACCCCGGUGACAGUGAGGAAGACACCGAGCUCUCCUGUACCCGAGGAGGCUGUCUGGCCAGCCGCGUGGCCUCCUGCAGCUGUGAGCUCCUGACUGAUGCAGUCGACCUGCCCCGCCCCCCAGAGACGACAGCCGUGGGUGCAGUGGUGACAGCCCCCCACAGCCGAGGUCGAGAUGCCGUCAGAGAAUCCCUGAUCCACGUCCCGCUAGAGACCUUUCUGCAGACCCUGGAAUCCCCGGGCGGCAGCGGCAGUGACAGCAAUAACACAGGGGAACAGGGUGCAGAGACGGAUCCCGAGGCUGAACCCGAGCUGGAGCUAUCCGACUACCCAUGGUUCCACGGGACACUGUCCCGGGUCAAGGCUGCUCAACUGGUUCUGGCAGGGGGGCCCCGGAACCACGGCCUCUUCGUGAUCCGCCAAAGUGAGACUCGGCCUGGGGAGUACGUGCUGACCUUCAACUUCCAGGGCAAGGCCAAGCACCUGCGCCUGUCCCUGAACGGCCACGGCCAGUGUCACGUACAGCAUCUGUGGUUCCAGUCUGUGCUUGACAUGCUCCGCCACUUCCACACACACCCCAUCCCACUGGAGUCAGGGGGCUCGGCCGACAUCACCCUUCGCAGCUAUGUGCGGGCCCAGGACCCCCCACCAGAGCCGGGCCCCACGCCCCCUGCCGCGCCCGCGUCCCCGGCCUGCUGGAGCGACUCGCCCGGCCAGCACUACUUCUCCAGCCUCGCCGCGGCCGCCUGCCCGCCUGCCUCGCCCUCCGACGCCGCCGGCGCCUCCUCGUCUUCCGCCUCGUCGUCCUCUGCCGCGUCGGGGCCCGCCCCCCCGCGCCCCGUCGAGGGCCAGCUCAGCGCGCGGAGCCGCAGCAACAGCGCCGAGCGCCUGCUGGAGGCCGUGGCCGCCACCGCCGCCGAGGAGCCCCCGGAGGCCGCGCCCGGCCGCGCGCGCGCCGUGGAGAACCAGUACUCCUUCUACUAGCCCGCGGCGCCGCCCGGGUGGGACACGCCAAGCUCUUCAGUGAAGACACGAUGUUAUUAAAAGCCUGUUUUAGGGACUGCA